AAGUUCUGCCUUGUCUCCGCCGCGGGUCAGGGGUGAGAGCUGGAAUCUCUGCACGGGCCUUGGUGAGUAACUGCUGCGAGUUCUGUUCCCGCGCGGCGCCAGUUCAAAGAACUUAGGUUAGAUCACGCUUAGGGCCCAACAGGACUGUGCCAGGCCUCAGGAGUCUCCACCCUCUCCAGUUUUGGGGCCGUCAGUCUCCUGGGCCUGCAAUUAUCCACGCUGAGGCUGAGGUCUUUGGCUUUUAGCGAGUUGGAUUGCAGCCUUGUUCUGCUUCUGUGUCUUCUCUCUCCAGGCGAGGUCCUACUGAGGUUGUUGCCAGCGAUAGUCCUCUCCUGGAGCUUGAAUUGGAAGCAGAGUAGUCUUGUUAGUCUCGGUGAUGGCUGCGUUGUUUCCUGAAGUAGCCAAAGUGCUUUAGCAUCCAUUCCGCCUCCUUUGAGCACCCUGGGAGGAAAACGACUGUCUUCUUCUGCCAAAAUGUCAGGAAUUGGAAAUAAAAGAGCAGCUGGAGAACCUGGCACCUCCAUGCCUCCUGAGAAGAAGGCAGCUGUUGAAGAUUCAGGGACCACAGUGGAAACAAUUAAGCUAGGAGGUGUCUCUUCAACGGAGGAACUAGACAUUAGAACACUGCAAACCAAAAAUCGCAAGCUGGCAGAAAUGUUGGAUCAGCGGCAGGCCAUUGAAGAUGAACUUCGUGAGCACAUUGAAAAACUGGAACGACGACAGGCCACUGAUGAUGCCUCACUAUUGAUUGUCAACCGAUACUGGAGUCAGUUUGAUGAAAACAUCCGUAUCAUCCUUAAACGUUAUGAUCUGGAGCAGGGCUUGGGAGACCUACUCACAGAACGAAAAGCCCUUGUUGUGCCUGAACCAGAACCAGACUCUGAUAGCAAUCAGGAGCGUAAAGAUGACCGAGAGAGAGGGGAAGGGCAAGAGCCAGCUUUCUCUUUCCUUGCUACUUUGGCCAGCAGUUCCAGUGAAGAGAUGGAGUCUCAGCUGCAGGAACGUGUGGAGUCUUCCCGCCGAGCCGUGUCCCAGAUUGUGACUGUUUAUGAUAAAUUGCAAGAAAAAGUGGAGCUCUUAUCCCGGAAGCUAAACAGUGGAGAUAAUCUGAUAGUGGAGGAAGCAGUGCAGGAGCUGAACUCUUUCCUCGCACAGGAGAAUAUGAGGCUACAGGAAUUGACAGAUCUUCUUCAGGAAAAGCAUCGCACCAUGUCUCAGGAGUUCUCCAAGUUGCAGAGUAAAGUGGAGACAGCCGAAUCACGAGUGUCUGUCCUGGAGUCCAUGAUUGAUGACCUGCAGUGGGAUAUUGACAAAAUUCGAAAGAGGGAACAGCGACUCAACCGACACUUAGCAGAAGUCCUAGAACGGGUGAAUUCCAAAGGUUAUAAGGUGUAUGGAGCGGGGAGCAGUCUGUAUGGCGGCACAAUCACUAUCAAUGCUCGGAAGUUUGAGGAAAUGAAUGCAGAGCUUGAGGAGAACAAAGAGUUGGCUCAGAACCGUCUCUGUGAGCUGGAGAAACUUCGGCAAGACUUUGAGGAGGUCACUACACAAAAUGAAAAGCUGAAGGUGGAAUUGCGGAGUGCAGUGGAGCAAGUCGUUAAGGAAACUCCAGAAUAUCGCUGCAUGCAGUCACAGUUCUCCGUCUUGUAUAAUGAGAGCCUACAGUUGAAAGCACACUUGGAUGAGGCUCGGACCCUGCUUCAUGGCACCAGAGGAACCCACCAGCACCAGGUUGAGCUUAUUGAGCGAGAUGAGGUUAGUCUUCAUAAGAAGCUGAGGACUGAAGUAAUUCAGCUAGAAGAUACAUUGGCCCAGGUCCGCAAGGAGUAUGAAAUGCUGAGGAUAGAAUUUGAGCAGACCCUUGCUGCCAAUGAACAAGCAGGCCCUAUAAACAGGGAGAUGCGCCACCUCAUCAGUAGCCUCCAGAAUCACAAUCACCAGCUGAAAGGGGAGGUCCUGAGAUAUAAGCGGAAAUUGAGAGAAGCCCAGUCUGACCUGAACAAGACACGCCUGCGUAGUGGUAGUGCCCUCCUGCAGUCCCAGUCUAGUACUGAGGACCCGAAGGAUGAGCCUGCGGAGCUAAAACCAGAUUCUGAGGACUUAUCCUCCCAGUCCUCAGCUUCAAAGGCAUCUCAGGAGGAUGCCAAUGAAAUCAAGUCUAAACGGGAUGAAGAAGAACGAGAACGAGAAAGGAGGGAGAAGGAGAGGGAACGAGAAAGAGAACGGGAGAAGGAGAAGGAGAGAGAACGAGAGAAGCAGAAGCUAAAAGAGUCAGAAAAAGAGAGAGAUUCUGCUAAGGAUAAAGAGAAAGGCAAACAUGAUGAUGGACGGAAAAAGGAAGCAGAAAUUAUCAAACAAUUGAAGAUUGAACUCAAGAAGGCACAGGAGAGCCAAAAGGAGAUGAAACUAUUGCUGGAUAUGUACCGUUCUGCCCCAAAGGAACAGAGAGACAAAGUUCAGCUGAUGGCAGCUGAGAAGAAGUCUAAGGCAGAGUUGGAAGAUCUAAGGCAAAGACUCAAGGAUCUGGAAGAUAAAGAGAAGAAAGAGAACAAGAAAAUGGCUGAUGAGGAUGCCUUGAGGAAGAUCCGGGCAGUGGAGGAGCAGAUAGAAUACCUACAGAAGAAGCUAGCCAUGGCCAAGCAGGAAGAAGAAGCACUCCUCUCUGAAAUGGAUGUCACAGGCCAGGCCUUUGAAGACAUGCAGGAGCAAAAUAUCCGUUUGAUGCAGCAAUUGCGGGAGAAGGAUGAUGCAAAUUUCAAGCUCAUGUCAGAGCGUAUCAAGUCCAAUCAGAUCCAUAAGUUGCUUAAAGAAGAGAAGGAGGAGCUGGCAGACCAGGUGUUGACUCUGAAGACUCAGGUUGAUGCCCAGCUACAGGUAGUAAGGAAACUGGAAGAGAAGGAGCAUCUGUUACAGAGCAACAUUGGCACAGGGGAGAAAGAGCUGGGUCUUAGGACCCAAGCCUUAGAGAUGAAUAAACGCAAGGCAAUGGAGGCAGCCCAGCUUGCAGAUGACCUCAAAGCACAACUGGAGUUGGCUCAGAAGAAGCUACAUGAUUUUCAGGAUGAGAUCGUGGAGAACAGUGUUACCAAAGAAAAGGACAUGUUCAAUUUCAAACGAGCCCAGGAGGACAUCUCUAGACUUCGCAGGAAGCUGGAGACCACAAAGAAACCAGACAAUGUACCCAAGUGUGAUGAGAUUCUGAUGGAAGAGAUUAAGGAUUACAAGGCACGCUUGACCUGUCCGUGCUGUAACAUGCGUAAAAAGGAUGCUGUUCUUACUAAGUGUUUUCAUGUCUUCUGCUUUGAGUGUGUGAAGACACGCUAUGACACCCGCCAGCGCAAAUGUCCCAAGUGUAAUGCUGCUUUUGGUGCCAAUGAUUUUCAUCGCAUCUACAUUGGUUGAUCUAAGUCAAGAGAAGAAGAGGAGCUGGCUAGUCAGGAACUUAUUCAUUAACCACCAAACCUCUACCUCUUCUCUCCUUGACUGUCACCUGUAGGACAGUUUAUCAGUCAACUACCUUUCCUCCAGACUUUACUUCCAGGCUCUCCUCUUCAGUAGCUGGAUGACUUUAGCAGAAAGGACUGGUAAAUACAAGCCUUGGGUUUCAGAAUGAAUUAGAAACAAAUAACUCUUACUGUCUUCCCUCCCAGCUUUGUUUAUUUUGUGCUUUUAGACUUUUCAGUGUUUUCUUUUUCCAGCCCACUGUAUAAACUUGGAUUGUCCAUUCCUCCUGAAGAAAUCAAGUUGGUAUUUUUGAUGUGGAAAAGGGAACAAAAGUGGAAACAUGGCUACUUUUGGGGAGUGAUAUUUUAAAAAAUAAGUUGUCUAUGGGCACAAAGUUUUCUUCAUUUGUGUAGCAAACUUCUUGUGAAUGUGGAUUACAAAAUGGUAUAAUUGUGCUACUCUCCCCUGGGUGGUUUGCAGCCCUAAUGAAAUUAUGUCUAGGAUGAUUCAGUCUAUUUCCCAUUUACUAGCAGAGUAACUUGUUAAGAUCAGCUGGCUUUCUUGUUAAAGUUAUUUAAGUUUUGAAUGCUCUACUACUUCAAGUCUUUAAAUUUCUUGAGACUAGAAUAAUUUUAAAUAAUAUGACCCUUUGUCUUCUAAUGAAAUAAAGAUUGAAGAGGUUGAGUCAGGACUGAGCUGGUGAAGAAAUCUUGUGGGUAUUCUGGAAAUUUGAUACGGAGAGAACUUGGUGAGCUAUGAAUUACUCUCAGUCUCCUUUUUACAGGGUUGUUGUGAUCCCUCUUUUCCAGAAAAUUCUGUGGAAUGUUUCUGUAGGACUUUGUUCUCCACAAGCUUGAAUUAAAGCAGGAUUCAGUUUGCA